AAGCAGACACCAGCACUGCUCUUUCUCCAAGACGGCCGGCCAUGCUCUCCUCCUCUGCCAGUCUCCUCCACCACUCUCUAACCUGAGAGCCUGUGGAACCUGCCCGUCUCCCCUCCUCCAUCAGACACACCUGCCUAGGAAACAGGAAAGGACCUCGGAAGUCUUCUAAGGAGAGUCAUGGCGUAUUACCAGGAGCCUUCAGUGGAGACCUCCAUCAUCAAGUUCAAAGACCAGGACUUUACCACCUUGCGGGAUCACUGCCUGAGCAUGGGCCGGACGUUUAAGGAUGAGACAUUCCCUGCAGCAGAUUCUUCCAUAGGCCAGAAGCUGCUCCAGGAAAAACGCCUCUCCAAUGUGAUAUGGAAGCGGCCACAGGAUCUACCAGGGGGUCCUCCUCACUUCAUCCUGGAUGAUAUAAGCAGAUUUGACAUCCAACAAGGAGGCGCAGCUGACUGCUGGUUCCUGGCAGCACUGGGAUCCUUGACUCAGAACCCACAGUACAGGCAGAAGAUCCUGAUGGUCCAAAGCUUUUCACACCAGUAUGCUGGCAUUUUCCGUUUCCGGUUCUGGCAAUGUGGCCAGUGGGUGGAAGUGGUGAUUGAUGACCGCCUACCUGUCCAGGGAGAUAAAUGCCUCUUUGUGCGUCCUCGCCACCAAAACCAAGAGUUCUGGCCCUGCCUGCUGGAGAAGGCCUAUGCCAAGCUGCUCGGAUCCUAUUCCGAUCUGCACUAUGGCUUCCUCGAGGAUGCCCUGGUGGACCUCACAGGAGGCGUGAUCACCAACAUCCAUCUGCACUCUUCCCCUGUGGACCUGGUGAAGGCAGUGAAGACAGCGACCAAGGCAGGCUCCCUGAUAACCUGUGCCACUCCAAGUGGGCCAACAGAUACAGCACAGGCGAUGGAGAAUGGGCUGGUGAGUCUCCAUGCCUACACUGUGACUGGGGCUGAGCAGAUUCAAUACCGAAGGGGCUGGGAAGAAAUUAUCUCCCUGUGGAACCCCUGGGGCUGGGGCGAGGCCGAAUGGAGAGGGCGCUGGAGUGAUGGGUCUCAGGAGUGGGAGGAAACCUGUGAUCCGCGGAAAAGCCAGCUACAUAAGAAACGGGAAGAUGGCGAGUUUUGGAUGUCGUGUCAAGAUUUCCAACAGAAAUUCAUCGCCAUGUUUAUAUGUAGCGAAAUUCCAAUUACCCUGGACCAUGGAAACACACUCCACGAAGGAUGGUCCCAAAUAAUGUUUAGGAAGCAAGUGAUUCUAGGAAACACUGCAGGAGGACCUCGGAAUGAUGCUCAAUUCAACUUCUCUGUGCAAGAGCCAAUGGAAGGCACCAAUGUUGUCGUGUGCGUCACAGUUGCUGUCACACCAUCAAAUUUGAAAGCAGAAGAUGCAAAAUUUCCACUCGAUUUCCAAGUGAUUCUGCAUCCCAUCGACGUUGUGAGCUGUCCUUCCAAGAAGCAUCUUUCAGCCCACCCCAGCCUGAGAUAGUUUCCAGGGCUUUCAGACGAGAAUUCCUGCUGACUCUGGUGCCUUCUAAGAGGACCCUCAGAUUUUCCAGCUCUCACCUCUGGGAAGAAAAGGCUAAAGGCAGAAGGAGAGAUUUGUGAAAGGCUGAGAAGGAACUGAGGCCCCUGGUCUGCCCAGCCAGGACUGACCAGGUCAAGCACCAAAGAGGCCUACUAGAAACAUCUCAGCCAACUCUUCCUUCUUCUGAGCUAAGACAGAAGCCCACAGAAGGAUCAGAGCUGCCCCGGCACACACGCAACUUCUGAGGCUCUGUUCACAUGGGUGACCAUGGGCCUUGUGUUGAUUCACCCAAAGUCUUCACAGUUCAGGAACCCUACCAAGAUUGUAACCACCCCAUUUUUAAAAUGACAUCAAGCCCACUUUCCUACUUUUCUGCCAGAGAUGUGUUACUUCUCACCAUUCACCAAUUUGCUGAAGGAACUCUCAGACCCAAGAGCUCCUCAGGCUUCCUGGAGAUCCCAGCAGAUCUUGCAAGAUCCUGAUUGAGUUAAAUGUCAAAGAACAGUUCAGACCUGGACAACUCAAAUGACACUGGUUGCUUUCACAGUUCAGCUGAGAAACAACAAUGUACCUGCCAGCAGCCAGGCUCUCAGAAGGCUCCAGGGCUCAAAUGGAGUUCCAGGGCUCCAGUGCUGACCUGCUGAUAUGAUGAUGCUCCAGCCCUGGCAUGGGUCUGUGACUCCCCAGUUGCUGUGGGAGCACUGCUCUGCUUUAUGUCCAACCAGACCUUGAUGGGAUAUGAAUAGGCAGGGAGAAGACAGGACAGUGAAAAGGAUGAGGGUGGAUGAGCCAUUUCAUCCUCACCUCCCUCAAAGUUCCUCCCCAAGGCCUGGACUUUCCACCUUCCUCCCAGCUCACCCUUGGCCUCCAGAGAAGUCGGCUAAGAGGUCUGUACACAUGGGUGGGGCCCAGUGUCAACAAUGGGAAAUAAUCAAGCCAACUAAGGAAGACAUCACCUGGUGGUGACAGGGCUUGACUACAAAGCAAGCAGCACAGCUUCCCCGAUUCCCAGCUCUGCUACUUAAACUGCUGAGCCUCAGUUUCUACACCCAUAAAAUAGGGAGCCCAGCAUCGGCUUGCAGGAUUAUUGUGAAUAUCCAACACAUUACAUAAAAGUGCUUUGCAAACCGUAGAGAGGCUUACAAUGGAACUGCAUUCUCAGGUAUUCCUUCUACUACGUGAAAAGACUGGAACAUGGGUAUCUCCCCAUUCAUAGGCACACAGACAUUCCUACAAGCAUCAGGGGUGGGAGUGCAAGAACGAAUUCCCAUCUAUUUACAGUGGCCUGAUAGAAUAAAAGAAGUUGACUUCUCAGGGAAGCUCCCGAUGUUAGGGAGCUUACAUUUGCGCCAGGUUCUGUGCUAUCUGUCAAAAUCUCCCCCUUCCUUUCAGUGCGAUCAUCAUUGCUGUGAAGAGUAACCACACCUUUCAGGGCUGACCAAAGAAUACCUCCUCCUCUCAGACACCUCCUUUUCUGCCUCAGUUUCCUUCCUCUUGCUGUUCUCUGCAAUUGAGUGGGUUUCAUUUUUCACAACCUCACACAGAGCAUGAGUGACCAGUCAUCCCAGUUCACCUCUAGGUGUGCCAAGGAACAGGCAGGCCACACAAGGAAGAGGAACGUGUUCCACUUAUAAAUUUUUUGAGGUUAUCCUCAUUGAUCCAUUCCAUAAAACUAUCAGAGGAAAUCUUGACACCCAGCAGAUCACCAAAUCUAUCCACAAGCAUGGGGAGAUGUGUGGGCUGACAUCCUCAGGCUGCAAGAGCCAUGGCCUUGGAAAGGGCCGUAAGUUCUACCACGCUAUUGGUGGUUCUCACCAUGCAACUUGGAGAAGGUGCAAUAUUCUCCAGCUCUAAUGUUAUCACAGAUAUAAGUAACGUUUGUAAAAUUCAUACCUAAUAAAUUUAGAACAGUCA